ACAGGUAAACAGAAGUAACUAUCAUUUGGGGUUGUCAAGAUAUGGGUAGUAGAUACCUAAUUCCAUGAAUGCCUUCUCUGUGCAAGUGCUGGAAAGUAACCUCAGACUUCCAGACUCAUCACUGAGAUUCUUUUUCUUAAGCAAAAUAGUGACGCUCUGCAGGAUUUCUAUAACUGAAGUUCUCUAAAAGAUAAAUUUAUAUUGCAUUAAGAGGGUAGAGGGUAGUAUUUAGAGCUAUGCUCUCUUAAAAAGAGUAAAGAAAUUUCAUGUAUAUGAAGGAACAGAAAGCAUGGGGAUAAGUUUUAUACACCCUAGAGUGGACUUUUAUGAUAAAAAGUAAUUUACUUGUUAAUCAAUUUAAUUCAGCAAUGGGAAAAGAUCUUUCUCUUCUUUCUGAAAUCUUACACAGUGAAGGGAUGAAAAUGGUUAUACUAUUGGUAAUCAGAGAUGUUCCUAUUUUGUUUUGAUGUGUAGAUUCCGUAGUACCUAGUGUUGUUGGAUAUUAAGAAAAAUUCUAAUCCCUGUUCUUGUGGGAAUUGCACAAGGAGCAAUGUAAACACAGGUAGUGGAGGUAGAGAUGUGCUGUCGUCUACUUCUGCUCUAACUUGAGCAGCCACAUCUCACUCAGGGUCAUCCCAUAGGAUGUCCAGGCUGUGGUUGGAGAGAAGUGGGGGGAUGAAGACGUGGGGUGCAAUAAUGGGAGGAGGAUGGGCUUUGGGACCAGAAGGUUGUGAAUUUGAGUUCUGGUCCAUCUUCUUGGCAGCUGGGUCGAUUAGGGUGGUGAAUUAGCUGGCUGAAUUACUUCACACAUCAGAGCCUCACUUUCCUGGUUUGUAAAAUGCAGAUUGUGCCCCUCUCCCAGGGCUGCCAUGAGGGUUAGGGAGGCCAGGAAUUAAAACAUGUAAACCAUGCAUUACACUGCAUUUCAACCCCUGCAAGGGUGAUGCAGCUAGCUUUACCUGAUUUUACUUGGAUUGUUUCUUUUUUUUUUUUGAGACGGAGUCUCGCUCUGUCACCCAGGCUGGAGUGCAGUGGUGUGAUCUCGGUUCACUGCAAGCUCCACCUUCCGGGUUCACGCCAUUCUCCCGCCUCAGCCUCCCAAGUAGCUGGGACUACAGGUGCCCGCCACCAUGCCUGGCUAAUUUUUUUUUUUUUUUGUAUUUUUAGUAGAGACGGAGUUUCACCGUGUUAGCCAGGAUAGUCUCGAUCUCCUGACCUCAUGAUCCGCCUGCCUCGGUCUCCCAAGGUGCUGGGAUUACAGGCGUGAGCCACCGCGCCCGGCCUGGAUUGUUUCUUUAGUGAAGAAAAGACUGGGGAGAAGGGCACUUCUUAAAGCAAUGUCAACAGCCUCUCAUAUAGUUAAUACAUCUCUAUGUGGCCCUUCCCAGAGUGUCCUUCUGUGAGGAGAUCCAUUACAAAUACAAAAAAUUCAUGUGGCCAGAUAAGUUCUAUGACCAGAUAAGUCUGGCAAAAGCUGUUUAUUAUACCUGCCUCUUAAAGAUUCACAAGGCUGAAAAGUCCUGAAGGAAUGUAACUUUCUCUAACCCAGAAUUUCACAAACUUAUAUGAAAACAAAAUCUUUAUUUAGUAUGAUAACCUAUUGGCAUCAAUUCAUAUAUUAUUUCAGUAAAUGUUGGAGACUUUCUGUGUGCCACAGACACCUUCACAGGCUGCUUCAGCGAGGACUGGGGGAGGGAGAGAGAGAUGAGUAAAAAGAUUGAAAUGAUGAUUCCAGAUCAUGAGGGAUACGUUGAAUAUAAUAAAUCAGUGUGGGUAUUCUGGGUGAGAAGUGAGAGCUAUUUCAGAUCAGAUGGUCAUAAAAGGCCUCUUGAAGAGGUGAUAUUUGAGCUGGAAUCUGAAUAAUUCAAGUUAACUGGCCUUGCAAAAAUCUUGGAGGGUAGAACCUUCUAGGCAGAGAUAAAAGCAAAGGAAUUAGUGUUCUUGAGAGCACACUUUGAGGAAAGCUGUUGCAAUAAGAGCAAAGAGCAUGUAUAAGAAGUAUUUCAAUCAAAUUUUUAUAUACAAAAUAUGUAGUAAAUCUUUUUCGAGCAUUAUGUGCUAGAUACUAUGUGCCACAGACACAGAGAUGACAGUUACAUUUAAAGAGUAGAGUAGUUCGGAGAAGAAAGACUCAACAUCUAGGGGAUUGAGUGAUAAGUUGCAUGGUGGAGGUAGCAUGUUGUAGUGGCUGAGGUUAGAGCCAGACUGCCCAAGUUCAGGUCCUAGAUCCGCCACUUACUUGAUAACCUUGGGCAAGCUACUGACAUCUGCAUGCGAACACUGGGGACAUUCCUAGUGCCUCUCAGUGGAUUGUUAGUAUAUGCAAAGUUGUUAGGACAGUGCCUGGAACAUAAGGACCACAUGCUAAAAUUGAAGAUGAUGAUGUUAGAGAUAUUCCCGUCAUAACCAUCAUCGUUACAGUUGUCAUCACUGUAAUCUUUUAGUGCCAUGGUCCAGCUCAGAUGCCUGAGUCUUCAUGCCCUCCUAAUGGGCCCCAGGUUUGCCCAUCAGAGUCUUACACAUGAUCACCCACACCAUGUAGGCACUAUUCUUACCCAGCAAAGAGAUUAAAACUUGCUUCAUCUGUUUUCUACCCAAUUUAACUUUGUUAACCACCCUCUUAAAAAGAAGUUUCUUGAGGAUUUAUCUCUGGUUGUCUUCCAGUUUGGGCGGCGGGUGGUGGGUGGUGAUAGUUGGUAAUAGGGUUGAGGUAGGAUGGAAUAAAUCAGAAUCUGCAAUGAACCACUUGCUGGAUAAUUAGGGUAGAUGAGAACCACAGGACUGUAAUAAAAAUGGAUUAUCAUAACGAUGACCCUACGGUGCUAAAUGAUGCACCAUGUUCCUUUUGAAUCAACAAAAGUUAAAGUCUUCCUGGAAUAGUUUUAGUACAUUAUUGAUCUCUAAUUCUUAGAAAAUUGGCAAUCCAUGUAUAGAAUAAGAAAGUCUCUAUUGCUGCAAAUAUUCAUAACCUGAAGAACCCAUUCCCUAACCAUUUUAGAUAAAUAAGAUUUUUAUAAAAUUAAAGCAAUUAUUAAAAUUCUAUUUGUGCAUGGAAGAAGCCAUUUAGCUAACCAAUUAUAUAUCUAACUUCUGUAACAGCACUUCGGAAUUAAUCUAAUUGCAUCCUAUUGAAAGUCAGUCACCUUUUGCAACAUGACAAUUUUAUGCCAAGAGAAUGAAAAUGUCAGGUAUUUCCAUUACAGAGAGUCACAUUUUCCCUUGAUUGUUUCAGGCAGAAAGAAAGCGACUCAGAUUAAUCUGUUUAGAACUAUUUUCAGUUAUCUGUAUAUGUCAUACAUGCUGUCAUGUUCUAAGACCACUUUGUUCUUGGAUACUGCUUUCCAAAAUCUAUGGGAUUCUACUCUUAAAAAAAAAAAAGAAUAUCUCGCUUUACAUAUCAUUUUAUUCUGGGGAAGCCUAAUUAGCACAUUAAUAUCAGAGAGCUGACAACCUCCUACAUGUUAUUUUAGGAUUCCAUGUGCAAGACCAUAUUAUUCUAGUUAUUUGAAUGGCACGUAUUCUCCACAGCUUGCUAACAGUAGUUUUGUCUUUUAAAAUUUAUGUGUUUCCAGUGUUUAGGGUCUGCUAAGGAGUGGGAGGUGAAUGUGUCAUCAUAAAGAAUGUUGCAGCAAAUAUAUUUUGCAGGAUACAGCCAUUUCCAUUUUUUGUAGUACAAAGAUCCUAUCAUCCUGAAAUCUUACAUUGUAGAUUGUGUUAUGUGCUGCUUUUUAUUUCAGUGAGAUGAAAGUAAUAUUCUGAAUGAGAAAAGAAUUAGAGUAGCAUUUCUCAAAUGCCAGUUUUGAACCUAAGUUUAAAAUAGAGAGAUUUAUCACUGAAAAGAUUAAGAGAAAAGAAAGAACAUUUAUGGAAUAGGGAUUACACUAGGUAUUUUCAUAGAGGUAUUUAAUUCUUGCAGUCAACCUUCAAGAUCUGUGAGAUUUAUCCAUCACAAAUAAAUGUGUUCAGAUUAAGUAUGUGGCCUAGCAAUUUUGUAAAUUACUGUUUUUUACUUUGCAUUUAACAUUUAUGUAAUUCCAAGCCAAUAUUUUGAACCUACUUUUAACAGUUACAUAAGACCUUUUAGAAUGAAUUUUGUAUUUAUCUUUUUUCUCCUGAUUUUCUGGCCUUCAUUUUUCUGCCAAAUAUUUUAAAAAAUAGUGUUUUACUGUAUGUUUUUAGAUAAGCCACCUCAUGCCAUUCUUGAUAUAAGUUGUGGUUAUUAAAUUAAUUUAAUAAAUUAACUAAUUAUAAACUUGGCCAAAGUCACACAGGUAAGAAAUGGUAGGUCCAAAUAUAUAAACCUAAAUAUGAUAAAUUUCCAAGUACUUGCUGUUCUCUUUGCACCUUGCUGCCUUAUGGAAUCAAGGUAAAAAUAAAGAAAAAAAUGUAAGUGCUUUGAAAGGGUUCACAGCUAUUUGUAUAACUAGAAUAUAAUCUAUUUUGAGCAAAGAGAAUUGGGUUAUAUAUCUUAUUUCUAGAUUGGGCCAAACCAGUAAGUCAUUUUCGGUUUACAGGAUUCAAAUCAACAUUGUAUUAACAUUAAUGAAAAUGCCAACUCCCAUUCAGAGCAGAUGAGCAACAGGUGAUAUCAGAGAGGACCUCUUAGAAAAAGCACCUUUUUUUUCUAGUAACUGCUGAUUGUGUCCUACAACCUUCUGUGUUAAUUAGCUUGAAGUGCCUCAAUAAUGCAUCGGCCAGGUUGCCCAGAACCCUGCAAACAUCUUUUCAUCAUCCCUCAUGUUGUGGGCUUUCCUUAAUAGGAAGGCAGAUAACUUCAGAUCUUUAUGUCUCUUAGAUUUUAUAGUUUUGAAAAAGUGACAAGUCUUUUUGUCAAUAGAUGCCUGGGUCUUCUUAUACUUCUGAAGAGAGGAAAAUCAAUCCAAAAGAAAACACAAUAGAUUCUAAUUUUAUGGACUGUUCAUUAGGAAGUCUGGUUUUGCUUAAGACAACUGUGCUGGUCUAGAAGUUCAUAGUAUUUAUUGAUUUUUCUUCUUUCUGAUGAUCAUUAUUGCUAUUUUGUAGCAAUAUUGAUAUUGUAUAAUAUAAAUUCUUUUUAUUUUGCUAAAGGGAAGUGCUUCUGUAUUCUUGAAAACUGAGAAUCAAACAGUAUUUAAAGUACUUUUUCUGGUUUAUCCCCAGUGUCUGUCAUAGGGCAUAGCUCUAAAGAAGUUCACUCAGAUAUCAAGGGUGAAUGAAAAUUCUCUGAAAGAGAAGUACAAAUUAUUGUGGGUCCAACUCUUUACCAUACAUUAUAGAAGGCAGAGAAACCAUGACCACCUAAACUUGUAGGACACUGUGGGGAGAAGAGCCUAUGAAGUUGAUUCCUAAUGUAGGUCUGCAGUGGCCAUGGAGCUGAGAAAUCACCGAAAUGGGGAGGAGGAGGAGGGAUCUGUCUGCCUAACUUCAGUAAUAUUAUUGCCUUUUCUUAGAUAACCCUCUUCACUCUUUUCUGUCUCCUCAAUCCUUAUCUAGCUGUCAAAGUCUCGUUCAAAUCCUGCCUCCUCCAGGAAAUCUUAUCUGCUCACUACAACUCAAACUGAUUUGUUGACCUGGCCAUUUACAGCAUUUGUUUGACCAUACCACCUGGCCCUUAAGGCUGCCUGGCGUUUUCUAAUAAAAGCUAUCAUUUUUCUGAAUACAGACUAUUUGCUUGCUUUUAUUUCUUAGCAGCUCCAUGAGAUACAUACUAUCAUUGUCCCAAAUUUAUAUUGUCUGUCUCUCCCUUCACAUCUAUUAAUAUUUGCUUUAUGUAUUUAGGUGUGCUAAUGUUAAGUGCAUAUAUAUUUAUAAUUAUUCUCUUGAUGAACUGUAUCCUAUACUACUAUAUAAUGACCUUCUUUAUCUCAUUUUACAGUACUUAAAGUAUAUUUUAUCUGAUACAAAUAUAGCUACCCUGAAAGUAUAGCUCUCUUUUGAUUUCAAUUUUCAUGGAUUUUUUUUUUUUUCAUUUCUUUACUUUCCGUCUAUGUGUCCUUACAGGUGAAGCGAAUCUGUUAUGGACAGCAAUAGUUAGGUCUUGUUUUUUUUUUGAGACGGAGUCUCGCUCUGUCACCCAAGCUGGAGUGCAGUGGCGCAAUCUAGGCUCUGCAAGCUCCGCCUCCUGGGUUGACACCAUUCUCCCACCUCAGCCUCCUAAGUAGCUGGGACUACAGGCGCCCGCCACCACGCCCAGCUAAUUUUUUGUGUUUUUAGUAGAGACGGAGUUUCACCGUUAGCCAGAAUGGUCUCGAUCUCCUGACUUUGUGAUCCUCCCGCCUCGGCCUCCCAAAGUGCCGGGAUUACAGGCGUGAGCCACCGUGCCCAGCCAGGUCUUGUUUUUUUAUCCAUUCAACCACUGUGUAUUUUUUGAGUGGAGAAUUUAAUCCAUUUACAUUCAAAGUAAUUAUUGACAGGUAAGGACUUAUUAUUGCCAUUAUGUUCACUACUUCCUGGUUGCUUUAUAAAUCCUUCAUUCUGCUCUUCUCUCUUGCUAUCUUUUUUAUGAUUAGGUGAUUUUCUCUGCUGCUAUGCCUUGAUUCCUUAUGAUUUAAAUUUUGAGUAUCCUCCUUAGGUUUUCUUUGUGGUUACCGUUAGGUUUAUAUACAACAUCAUCUAGUUAUAACAGGCUAUUUUAAGUUGAUAACAACUCAGAUUGCAUUAAAAAACUACACUUUUGCUCUACUUCCUCCCACAUUUUACGCUUUUGAUGCCACAAUUUAUAUUUUUAUAUUGUGUAUCAACAAAUUACAUUGUAGCUAUUAUUUAAAUAAUUUAUAUUUUAACCUUCAUACUAAAGUAUAAGUGAUGUAUACACCACUAUCACAGUAUUAUUCUGAAUUUGACUGUGUACUUUUACCAGUAAGUUUUAUGCUUUCAUAUGUUUUCAUAUUACUAAUUAGCAUCCUUUUCUUUCAGCUUGAAGAACUCCCUUUACUAUUUCUUAUAAGACAAGACUAGUGGUGAUUAACUCCCUCAGCUUUUGUUUGUCUGGGCAAGUCUUUUAUCUCUCCUUAAUUCUGAAGCACAGCUUAGCCAGAAUCUAUUGUUCCAUCAGACUCUGUUGUUACAUCUACAUUGAUUAGCUGGCCUUCUUCUGUAAAGGUGAGCAUUUCUUUAUCAACUGUGGGUCGACUACAGUUUCUUCUAAAAAGUUAGGGUAAUUUGUAAUCCUUCCCCUUUACCACGUUUCGAGUAGAUCUCACCAUAUCGAAUUUUUCCCAUUAUUUUUUCAGGGCUACUUUUCUUUCUGACACAACUAAAUUUGCUCACCUUCCAAUUUCCUGCCUCAGACCCCAAAUCAACCAUUUCUUCAAGGAACCUCAGUUCUUUUUAGUGAAGGAUGAUACCAGGAUAAAUGUGCUGCUUACCUUCAUUAUACCAGAGACAGCGUCUUGCUCUGUUGCCCGGGCUGGAGGGCAGUGGCACGACCAUAGUUCACUGCAGCCUCGAACUCCUGGCCUCAAGCAAUCCUCCCACCUCAGCCUUCCAAGUAACUGGGACUACAGACACACACCACCAUGCCCUGCUGAUUUAAAAAAAAUUUUUGUAAAGAUGGGGGUCUCUCUAUGCUGCCGAGGCAUGUCUCAAACUCCUACCCUCAAGAGAUCCUCCUGCCUCAGCCUCCCAGAGUGCUGGGAUUACAGGAAGACAGAGAUGUCAAUGACCCCAUGCCCAACCGAGGCGGCAAUGGACUAGCUCCUGGGGAGGACAGAUUCAAACCUGUGGUACCAUGGCCUCAUGUUGAAGGAGUAGAAGUGGACUUAGAGUCUAUUAGAAGAAUAAACAAGGCCAAAAAUGAACAAGAGCACCAUGCUGGAGGAGAUUCCCAGAAAGAUAUCAUGCAGAGGCAGUAUCUCACAUUUAAGCCUCAGACAUUCACCUACCAUGAUCCUGUGCUUCGCCCAGGGAUCCUCGGUAACUUUGAACCCAAAGAACCUGAGCCUCCUGGAGUGGUUGGUGGCCCUGGAGAGAAAGCCAAGCCAUUGGUUUUGGGACCAGAAUUCAAACAAGCAAUUCAAGCCAGCAUUAAAGAGUUUGGAUUUAACAUGGUGGCAAGUGACAUGAUCUCACUGGACCGCAGCGUCAAUGACUUACGCCAAGAAGAAUGCAAGUAUUGGCAUUAUGAUGAAAACUUGCUCACUUCGAGCGUUGUCAUUGUCUUCCAUAAUGAAGGAUGGUCAACCCUCAUGAGAACAGUCCACAGUGUAAUUAAAAGGACUCCAAGGAAAUAUUUAGCAGAAAUUGUGUUAAUUGACGAUUUCAGUAAUAAAGAACACUUAAAAGAAAAACUGGAUGAAUAUAUUAAGCUGUGGAAUGGCCUAGUGAAGGUAUUUCGAAAUGAAAGAAGGGAAGGUUUAAUUCAAGCACGAAGUAUUGGUGCUCAGAAGGCUAAACUUGGACAGGUUUUGAUAUACCUUGAUGCCCACUGUGAGGUGGCAGUUAACUGGUAUGCACCACUUGUAGCUCCCAUAUCUAAGGACAGAACUACAUGUACUGUGCCUCUAAUAGAUUACAUAGAUGGGAAUGAUUAUUCCAUUGAACCACAGCAAGGUGGGGAUGAAGAUGGUUUUGCCAGAGGGGCCUGGGACUGGAGUUUACUAUGGAAACGUAUUCCUCUAAGCCACAAGGAAAAGGCCAAAAGAAAACAUAAAACUGAACCUUAUCGGUCCCCAGCCAUGGCUGGGGGAUUAUUUGCCAUUGAACGAGAGUUCUUCUUUGAAUUGGGUCUCUAUGAUCCAGGUCUCCAGAUUUGGGGUGGUGAAAACUUUGAGAUCUCAUACAAGAUAUGGCAGUGUGGUGGCAAAUUAUUAUUUGUUCCUUGUUCUCGUGUUGGACAUAUCUACCGUCUUGAGGGCUGGCAAGGAAAUCCUCCGCCCAUUUAUGUUGGGUCUUCUCCAACUCUGAAGAAUUAUGUUAGAGUUGUGGAGGUUUGGUGGGAUGAAUAUAAAGACUACUUCUAUGCUAGUCGUCCUGAAUCGCAGGCAUUACCAUAUGGGGAUAUAUCGGAGCUGAAAAAAUUUCGAGAAGAUCACAACUGCAAAAGUUUUAAGUGGUUCAUGGAAGAAAUAGCUUAUGAUAUCACCUCACACUACCCUUUGCCACCCAAAAAUGUUGACUGGGGAGAAAUCAGAGGCUUCGAAACUGCUUACUGCAUUGAUAGCAUGGGAAAAACAAAUGGAGGCUUUGUUGAACUAGGACCCUGCCACAGGAUGGGAGGGAAUCAGCUUUUCAGAAUCAAUGAAGCAAAUCAACUCAUGCAGUAUGACCAGUGUUUGACAAAGGGAGCUGAUGGAUCAAAAGUUAUGAUUACACACUGUAAUCUAAAUGAAUUUAAGGAAUGGCAGUACUUCAAGAACCUGCACAGAUUUACUCAUAUUCCUUCAGGAAAGUGUUUAGAUCGCUCAGAGGUCCUGCAUCAAGUAUUCAUCUCCAAUUGUGACUCCAGUAAAACGACUCAAAAAUGGGAAAUGAAUAACAUCCAUAGUGUUUAGAGAGAAAAAAAUAAACCAAUAACCUACCUACUGACAAGUAAAUUUAUACAGGACUGAAAACCGCCUGAAACCUGCUGCAACUAUUGUUAUUAACUCUGUAUAGCUCCAAACCUGGAACCUCCUGAUCAGUUUGAAGGACAUUGAUAAACUGUGAUUUUACAAUAACAUUAUCAUCUGCAGUUACUGUUUACAAGACUGCUUUUACCUUAAACUUUGUAGAUGUUUACAUCUUUUUGUUGUGUUUUAAGAUGAUGUUGGUAAUUUGUGCCUUUAGCUCUGUUUUAUUAGACAGAGUUAAAGCAUGUUGUCUUCUUUGGGAUUACACUCAGGGGUCUGAAAGGCAGUUUGAUUUUUAUUUUUAACACACUUGAAAAAAGGUUGGAGUAGCCAGACUUUCAUAUAUAACUUGGUGAUUAUCAACCUGUUGUGUCUUUAUUUAAUUUUACAUCUUUUUGAAGCACUGCCACAGGUUAUUAGCCAAGGUGGCCUUCCUUCACAGUCAUGCUGCUUUUUUGAAAGGUGAAUUUCAACACAUUUAGUGCCUCUUUCAUUUCUCAGUAUAUAUUUCAAGAGCUUGUGAUGAAAUCUAUAGGAUGGUAAUGAUGGACUUGUCACCUGUAUGGGGAAUACUUUUACUACUCAGAAAUGAAUUUAUGUGCUGCCAUUUGCUAUAAAGUUGAACUUUGUAUGGCUUGAAAAAGAAAUGACAAUAUGGAACAUCCCAAGGCUGUCCCAUAGGGUUGGAAGUUGUGUAGCAUUCACUCCCUUACCUACUGGCAUUCCCAGUGCCCUCUGUCCAUACCUACUUCUAGGAUUGCAAAGGAGUCUUCCAACUAGAGAAAAAUUGUCCACUGACAUUUGGGAUUUACUUUUCUCCAAUACCUGCCAAUACAGAAAACUAUUAUCAGUUGUUAUUGUUAUCCCUUGAAAGCGAGGGUGACAAAAACAACAAAACACCGUUAUAAACACAUCAAAGGUUCAUUCUGACUGAGGUAAGACUUUCCAAGCCCUUGUUAGAUUAGGCCUUAUAAAACUUGUGUGCAUUAUAACCUAAGCUGUGCAACCUGUGAAGCCAAGAGUGAACUGAUGUUUCAUUUAUAUUUUCAUCCAAAUGACAUUAUCUGCACGUUUUUAAAAUUUAAAAACAAAGGACUAUUUAAAAAUACAGUUUAUUAACAAACGUGAACUACUUUCUGUUACAUUAGGUGUUCCCUAGUGUUUCUUAAUUUCUUUUUAGAAAGUGUAUUUUUAUUAGUAUUUUUCCGGUGAACAGAAGAUUUGUUUGGAUUUAAACAUUUACUAAGACAGUACCUAUUAGGAAAACCAAAUAUUGCAAAUGGUCAAUUCGAUUUUAAUUUCUCAAAAGAUACUCUGUUAUCCAGAAGAUUAAAAUGCCUACAUUGAGUGCUUAAAAAAAAAAAAACAACUGUGAUGAUGUGAGCAGAAUGGCAAGUAAGUUAAGCAUUUUUGAUCCUGUAAUCAUGGUAUCAUUACAAUGAAAGGAAUUCACAAACUACUGCCAGAGGAAGUUUGUUUUUUAAUUUAAGAGGGAAAUAUAACCUAUAAAUUUGUUUCUUCCAAGCUUAGCUCUUAAAUUUGGAGACUCAAAGUUAAACAUCCUCAACAGAGUUUUAUUUAUAAUUUUGAAUUGUCAAUUUGUAUUUUGCUACUGAUCUGUGAUCAACCAUUUUAACUUUCAUCUCUAGGGAUGUUUAACAUUUAUAAUUGCAAAAUAAACCAACUAUAAAAAAAGAAACUAAGAGAGAAUUGGUACUUUAAUUACUUGUGUGUUUGCAAAUAGGCUCCAUUUUCCAUGUUGAGUAGAUUAUAACCUUAUUAACUAUGCAUAGGCCUAAGAAAGGUGGCAAUGAACUGUGCAUGUAAAUUUUAAAUGGGUACUUUGUGCAAUUCGUUAAAAGAAGAUACUCUAUGAAUAUGAUUCUAUAUAUUGAAAUCAGAAAACCUACCAAACAAAAACAUCAGAAGCUGCUGCCAUAAUGACUAUUUUCUACUGUAGGCUGCUUUGGAAAUAAUUCCCAUAUCCUUGCUUUGUAAGUUGGUAAUAUCACUAUGCAUUUCUACACAUUUUAUAAAUUUGAUUUAUGCAGAUUUUGAUACACUGUAUGUUUCUGUAGAAAUUGUAUAAAUAUUCAAAAUUUUAUUAGGAUAAAUUUGAGAAACUUACGUAUAUCUUAAUUCUGGGUUGCUUGUUUUUUAGGUGACAAAAAUAAAAUAUUGUAUUUUAAUUCA